AUCCCGGCUGACGUUGGACGACAAAGAUGGCGGCAGGGACCAGCAGUUACUGGGAAGGUGAGGGCGAGAAGGCCUCCGGGUGCGUCCUACGAGGGUGAGAGGGGCUGAGUGAGGACAGAUCUUGGGAGAAGCAGCACAGGAAAGAACCAGACUCCCGGAGCGGCCGAGCUGAGCAGCGGGGCUUGCCUAAGUGGGAUCCCCGGGGCCUUGGGGAUACCGAACGGUCUGGGGUAGGGGUCUGGCCUGGCCGGGGCGUGUGAGCGGGACGUGGGGCAGGGGUUGGGCAGAGUGGACAGAGCGGGGAUGUAGAGGAAGAGGGCUCUCAAUCGCCUGGGUAGAAUUGUGUUGAGGGAGUAAUGGAACUCGGACGAAGGGGCUUGGGGUACGAACUCUGAGAGGAAACGAAUGUUGAGGGAGAAGAUCCAGAGCCCCGGAGACUGGAGGAGUCAGCGCAUUGGAGCUGAGGUCACUAUUGGAAAACUGAGUGGGAAAAGAGAAGGAGGAACUUGCAUUCCGGUCCGUCGGAGGAAGUAUGAAGAGAAUAGGAGACAGAAUGUCUCUUAUUGGGUCUCCAUGACAACUACAGAUCUCAGGAAACAGGCUCGACAGCUGGAAAAUGAACUUGACCUGAAACUAGUUUCCUUCAGCAAACUAUGUACAAGUUACAGUCAUAGCAGUACCCGAGAUGGAAGACGCGACAGGUAUAGUUCUGAUACAACACCCCUUUUAAAUGGAUCAAGCCAAGACAGAAUGUUUGAGACAAUGGCGAUUGAGAUUGAACAACUUUUGGCAAGGCUUACAGGGGUAAAUGAUAAAAUGGCAGAAUAUACCAACAGUGCAGGUGUCCCCUCCUUGAAUGCAGCCCUGAUGCAUACAUUACAGCGGCAUAGAGACAUAUUGCAGGAUUAUACACAUGAAUUCCAUAAAACCAAAGCAAACUUUAUGGCAAUACGGGAAAGGGAGAAUCUUAUGGGAUCAGUACGAAAAGAUAUUGAGUCAUAUAAAAGUGGGUCUGGAGUAAACAACAGAAGAACUGAGCUAUUUUUGAAAGAACAUGACCACCUUCGAAACUCAGAUCGUCUGAUAGAAGAGACAAUAAGCAUUGCUAUGGCAACAAAAGAAAAUAUGACUUCACAGAGAGGAAUGUUGAAGUCAAUUCACAGCAAAAUGAACACUUUGGCCAAUCGUUUUCCUGCUGUAAACAGCCUGAUCCAGAGGAUCAACCUGAGGAAGCGGCGGGACUCGCUCAUCCUAGGGGGUGUUAUUGGGAUCUGUACCAUCCUGUUGCUGCUGUAUGCGUUCCAUUGAUGGGACAUCUUCAGGGACUCUUGACAGCCACCGCUUUCACACCCUGGUCUGGAAUAAGGAAACAUCGGAGGGAGAAGUUGACUGUCUUGAUAAUUAGCCUGACCAGCAGGAUGAAUGCAAGACUGACAGUGAUGGACUCUGUGACAUGGUCAGGUUGAGCUGAAGCCACAGUUUCUCUGUGCUGUGUUUUCUAACACAUUUUUCUGUUUUUAAUUAAAAAAAAAAAAAAAAGGUUUUCAGUUGCUUUUGUCUCCCUAGGAGGCAGGUAAACCAAUCAAAAACAGAGUUUUCUGUGUUUCCAUGAUAGUGUUGAAGCCUAAUGACAAGCCAGGUCUUACAGCUGGGCUCUUCAGAAAACCAGGUUUCUACAUCCAAAGACUGCUUUUCUUUUAGCUGCCAGAUUGGAUUGUGAAUAAAAAUAAUUCUUCCCUCUCCCUCUCCCUCUCCCCACGGUCUCCCUCUUUCCACGGUCUCCCUCUGAUGCCGAGCCGAAGCUGGACUGUACUGCUGCCAUCUCGGCUCACUGCAACCUCCCUGCCUGAUUCUCCUGCCUCAGCCUGCCGAGUGCCUGCAAUUGCAGGCGAGCGCCGCCACGCCUGACUGCCUCGGCCUCCCGAGGUGCCGGGAUUGCAGACGGAGUCUCGUUCACUCAGUGCUCAAUGGUGCCCAGGCUGGAGUGCAGUGGCGUGAUCUCGGCUCACUACAACCUCCACCUCCCAGCCACCUGCCUUGGCCUCCCAAAGUGCCGAGAUUGCAGCCUCUGCCCGGCCGCCACCCCGUCUGGAAAGUGAGGAGCGCCUCUGCCCGGCCGCCAUCCCAUCUAGGAAGUGAGGAGCGCCUCUUCCCAGCCGCCAUCCCAUCUAGGAAGUGAGGAGCGUCUCUGCCCGGCCGCCCAUCGUCUGAGAUGUGGGGAGCGCCUCUGCCCCGCCGCCCCGUCUGGGAUGUGAGGAGCUCCUCUGCCCGGCCGCGACCCCGUCUGGGAGGUGAGGAGCGUCUCUGUCUGGCCACCCCGUCUGAGAAGUGAGGAGACCUCCGCCCGGCAGCCGCCCUGUCUGAGAAGUGAGGAGCCCCUCCGCCCGGCAGCCACCCCAUCUGGGAAGUGAGGAGCGUCUACGCCCGGGCAGCUGCCCCGUCCGGGAGGGAGGUGGGGGGGUCAGCCCCCCGCCCGGCCAGCCGCCCCGUCCGGGAGGGAGGUGGGGGGGAUCAGCCCCCCGCCCGGCCAGCCGCCCCGUCCGGGAGGGAGGUGGGGGGCGCCUCUGCCCGGCCGCCCCUGCCCGGCCGCCCCUACUGGGAAGUGAGGAGCCCCUCUGCCUGGCCACCACCCCAUCUGGGAGGUGUGCCCAGCAGCUCAUUGAGAACGGGCCAUGAUGACAAUGGCGGUUUUGUGGAAUAGAAAAGGCGGAAAGGUGGGGAAAAGAUUGAGAAAUUGGAUGGUUGCCGUGUCUGUGUAGAAAGAAGUAGACAUGGGAGACUUUUCAUUUUGUUCUGUACUAAGAAAAAUUCUUCUGCCUUGGGAUCCUGUUGAUCUAUGACCUUACCCCCAACCUGGUGCUCUCUGAAACAUGUGCUGUGUCCACUCAGGGUUAAAUGGAUUAAGGGUGGUGCAAGAUGUGCUUUGUUAAACAGAUGCUUGAAGGCAGCAUGCUCCUUAAGAGUCAUCACCACUCCCUAAUCUCAAGUACCCAGGGACACAAACACUGCGGAAGGCGGCAGGGUCCUCUGCCUAGGAAAACCAGAGACCUUUGUUCACUUGUUGAUCUGCUGACCUUCCCUCCACUAUUGUCCUAUGACCCUGCCAAAUCCCCCUCUGCGAGAAACACCCAAGAAUGAUCAAUUAAAAAAAAAAUAAUAUAAUAAUAAUUCUUGUCCUCUUAUUUUACACUCAUAAUGAGAAAUCACAAGUUCUUUCUUGAUGAUCUGUGCUAUAGAUUUCUACUCUGUCUCCUCAACUCUGUUGAUAUUUGGGGAAAAUUCUGUUUUUCAUAGAUUCUUUGAGAUGCUGAUGGACCAGCUUCAGCAUGUUUGAGGUUGUCUGAAAUGGAGAUCACUGUAAAACUGUCUUUUUCUUUUAAAUUACAAGUACACUGGGGUUAACUGUAUUGCUGGAAAAACAUCAAGAAUGACAGUCUUAUAUUUAAGGCACCAGUCAUUGUUUCCAUUUUUUUUUUAAUUCUUCCCUUGGAUUAAUAUUUUCUACUGAAAAGAAAUGAAAUCUCAGUUCCACUAUGAUAAAAGAAACGAAUCACCAGUGUCUGUCAGUGCCCCCACUGCUCCUCCUCAUACCAGCAUUGACACUGGUAGCUGAGGAAGGGGACUGCUCAAUUUCUAAUGUGAUCUAUUCAAGAAGCCACAUAUAAAAAGGCAUUGAGGGCUCACUGUCCAGAGAAUUGCUUUUGUAAAUGCUCCACAACGUAUGGGCAAAAGUUUAAGGACUACUGCCUGAUGUACCAGGAAUCCUGAGUUCUGUGAAAAUCUGUUCAUUCCAAAUCUGUUAAGCAUUUCCAAACAUCCAGAGAAUGGUUUCACUGUUGAGGGUGCAUGUGGCAGAAUCUGUCUCUCUCUGCACCUGUCUUCUGUUACCAUCCCUGGACAGUGACAGAUUUUAAGCCAGCCACCAGAAUUCUUUUCGAGUUAACCAUUUCUUAGUUUCUGUAAAUUCAUGACUUGUCUUACUGAACUACAGCCUGGUUUGUAGACUUCCAACAUCUACACUGCUGCUCUUCACCAUUGGAAUUCACUGUGGUAUUUAUAGUAUUGGCUUCAGUCCGAGCCACAGGCAAUAAAAGGAUAUCAGCUGUAGUUCUCAGCUACAUCAUGGUGUAUAGAUGCUGUUAUUCAGGCGAACUUGCUCAUGGGUGGACUAACACCUGGUUUGGUACAGAGACUGAGAAGUUUUUCAUUCUGGUGUCAAAGUUUUGUUACAUUAUGGGUGUGAAGGGCAUUUGAUAUAUUUUUCUUAACUAUGGGGUUUAUUUUUCUAAAUGUGGGUUGAUUGACUGUUAAUUGAUUCAGGGUACCCUUAAAAGAAAAGAAGUUUUCCCAUUGUGAACCUUAAAUGAUCAGAGAAGUAAGUUCAUUGAUUAAAUUCUCUGUUGGGAGAACAAAACUUUUCUCCCUUGACACUUUAUUAUCUUUGAUUUUUCAAAGGGCCUUGAUUGGUGGUUGUGUCUCGGUUAAAAUUUAUGGGACUUUGCUAUGUAGUUGGCAUUUAUAAAAUCUGAAGUAUCAUAAAUAAAGUUAUUUAUUUAAUUAUACUACCAGUCUUUUUUACUGGUCUGAUUCUUUUGUGCAUUCAUUAAAGCUGAUUGUGUGAGAGUGAACUGGGACACAAGCUAGUCUAGCUCACUGCAGCCAAGCAAACCCUGUUGAUGGCUGAUGGGCCUUUCCAUUAGGGUUUUGCUUAUGUGAAGUAAUGGAAUUAUGUUGGUUAUUUUCUUUAUGAAAAUAAACCAGUUCUUCCAAGGAAGUUAAAAGGCUUGGUAUGGAUGUUGGUGUCAGAUAGGUCUGACUAACCUCUCCGUGCUGCAGCCUAUACUAAGGUGACCCAGGGCCACAUGUAGACAGCUAGGCCAGUGCUUUUUCCUCUUAGGGUUUCUUUGCAGAAAGAAACCUCCAGCAAGGGAAGAGAGGUGUGUGUCCACAGGAAGGGGCUCCGUGGGGAUCCCAUGAAGGGAUUUGAGCUCUUUCAGCUCCAUGUCAUUUAACUUUUUUGUUUAACCACCUUGGCUUUCUCUCCUUUUUUGCUGUCCUCCUUACGGACCAGUUACCAGAUUCAGAGGCUAACAGUUAGUUACUUGUUAAUGCUAGUCACAGCCAGGAGGUCAGAAGGAAUUUUCUACUUCUGGAUCCAAAUGUUACCUCUUAGGGGAAGUUAUGCCCCCUCAACUAUUGUCUUAUUAUAAUGAAUCUUUCCUUUUUGGUCCUUUUAAGUAACCACUCAAAACUUUUCAUUUCACUGAAAAAAUAUGAAAAACCAUGACAAUAGGGCUGGGUGCAGUGGCUCACGCCUGUAAUCUUAGCACUUUGGGAGACCAAGGCAGGCGGAUCGUUUGAGGCCAGGAGUUUGAGACCAGCCUGGGCAAUGUAGCAAGACUCUGUCUCUGCAAAAAAAAUUAAAAGAUACCUGAGAGCUCACUUUAAUAUCAAGGUAUUUGCAUCCAUUCCCACCCUGUUAGCUCUUAAGGGAGGAGGGAAAUCAAUUCCAACCAUACUUUCCUGUGAUGGAAGAUGUUUCCUCUUGAAAAAAUGCCAAUACAGAUUUUUAAAACCUAUUGUUUUCCAAAUGCACUUUGUAAGUUUUUGCUUUUAAAAUAGCUUCUUGGAACCAAUUUUAUUGUAUUUGUACUUAAUUUUUGUUCUCAUCUAAAUGUGCAUUUUCUGACUGUAUAGAAGAAGCUUUGGUAUGUAAUUUAAUAAUAAAUUAGAAAUCUAAAUGAUUGCAUUUGUAAUUGUUUAUAUUGAAACAGUAACCAUCAAGGUAGUUUGGGGAUAGAGAUUAUGGUAUCUCUGGUGUUGAUAAGUGUUUCUCAUGAUGUCCUGAAACCCAGGAUGAAAUAAUACAGGUGCUGAAAAGCUGUCACAUGUCAUUCAGAAACCAUCAUAUGAACAGUCCACUAGUAUUUUAGCCCUAGAAGUGAAGGGGAAUCUCUUAACAUGAAACUUCAGGAGGCAUAAUGGGAAUCUACAAUUGUAGAAUUGGCUGGGUGCAGUGGCUAACACCUGUAAUCCCAGCAGUUCGAGAGGCCGAGGCAGGAGGAUUGCUUGAGACCAGGGAUUUGAGACCAGUCUGGGCAACACAGCAAAGACCUUGUCUCUACAAAAACUAAAAUUAGCCAUUCAUGAUGGUGUGCACCUAUAGUCCCAGCUACUCGGAAGGCUGAGGUAGGAGGAUCAUGAGCCCAGGAGGUCAAGGCUGCAGUAAGCAACGAUUGUGCCACUGUACUCCAGCCUGGGUGACAGAGACCCUGUCUCAAAAAUAAAUUAAUUUUUUAAAAAUCGUGUACUGCUGGGCUUUAGUACAUUAGUUGUGCAACCAGCCCCACUGUCUAAUUUUAGAGCUUUGCAAUUAAUCCAGCCAGUGAUCAAUUCCUCUUCUAUAAAAUGGUGAUAAGGAUGGCUACCAUAAUUGUGCCCUGAUUAUAUUGUCAGGGUUAUGUGAGGAAAUGCUCAUAAGCAUCUCAGCAAAGCCAGGGGUACAGGGCUCACCUGACAUAA